AGAACGCUUUGCCUCCUUUGAGUCCUUGGUUUUUGGGUGGUGCCCCCAUUUACAUUUGUGAAAUUAGGUCGCCUGUUUACUGAGCUGAAGGCAGCUUCUCUAAUUCUUCCUUCCAUGGGCCUCAGUUUCUCUGUAAGCAAAGGUGCUUCCCCAAGCUUUCUUGGGACUUAGACUGGAUCCAGGUCCAGCUUUCUUUAGGGAACGCGGAGGGGGAGAGUGGGGAGGAGGAAGAAAAUUAGCUUCAAGAAAGGGGAUAUGGCUCCAGGAACAUGGAUGGAAGAAGGAAAAGGGUCAGGAAGAGGGGAGAACAGUUAGGAUCCCCAUUGCAGGGGCAGGUAAAAAGGGGUCUGGUUGUCAGCUGUGUCACUUUGGAAGAGAGAGUGUUAAUAACAGCCUGGCUUUUGUUUUUUUCCUCCCCGUAUUUGAGUGCUCAGAUCCUGCAGAGGGAAGACUAAAAUGAAAUUAAAGACCAUAAGGAAUUGCCUUAGUUCAUUAUUAUUGUUAUUUUGUAGAGACGGUGAUUUUGCUGUGUUGCCCAGGCUGGUCUCGAACUCCUGGCUUCAAGCGAUCCUCCUGCCUCGGCCUCCCAAAGUGCCUAGAUUACAGGCAUGAGCUACCACCCCCGGCCAGGAAUUGCCUUAGAUAUUAACUGCAGAAUAAGGUGUUUUAAAAAUUUUCACAUUACAUUGCAGCUUAUUGAUUAAGACUGUGAACUGGUCCUAAUUUCCCUUUCCCACCGUUCCUGUUUAUGCUCAUUGCUUCAGGCAGAUUGGAUUUCUUUUUGCUCACAAAGAGUUCACCACACUUUGCUGCGUUGCUGUUUUUGCUUAAGAUGCAGUUGGAACUUGAUUACAUUUAUUCACCAUCAUCUGGCAAAGUGCUUGGUACAUGGAAGGCAGUCAGUACGUUUUUGCUGAAUGAAAUAUAAAAAUAAUAGAGGGAGGUCAGCUAGCCUAAGCAUAAGCCCAAGACACCCUUAUAGAAACAGAAAUACCAAUUGAAUACAGUGGAAUUGGCGUGGGACAUUGGGGCUUUUCCUUGCAAAUGAUUGGAUUGCUUGUGUCUGCUAUACUGGGUAUGGUAUUCUCAAUGUCAGGGUGCCCAGGAAACUGAAGUACUCAAUAGAAGGUUACUUAUGAGGAGGAAUUAGCACAGGGAGUUGUAAACUCUUGAGGGGGCUUUCAUAAGGUUAUGGGAAACUUUGGGGGUACUACUUCUGCUCCCUAUCCCCACACCCCCAUACACACACAGCAUACUUUUCAAGUUAAUUCAGCACACCUUAAGUAGGGUGCUGGGAAUAUGUUGAUGACUAAGAUACUUAAGGACUUCAUAGCCUAAGGUAGAAACACGUAACAGUGGGUCUCAGCUUUUUUGGUCUUAAGAUCUCUUGGCAUUCUUAAAAAUUACUGAGAAACCGAAAGAACUUUAUAUGGGUUAUAGCUAUGAGUAUUUACUGUAUUAGAAAGUAAAACAAAGUUAAAACACAAGAAUACACACACAUUCCAUUAGCUAUCAGAGUGAUGACUUCAUGCAUCAGGUAGCCUCUGGAAAACUCCACUGCACUUGUGAGAGAAUGAGAAUGAAAAAGGUACAUUACAUCUUAGUUUUGAACUCACGGAUACCCUGAAAGCAUAUCAGAGACCUUCCCACAUCUCCGGUCCCUUGAGUCACACUUUGAGAACAGAUGAUACAAAUAAUUAAAAUAUAGUUUGAUAUAUUUUUAGUAACAGUGACUGAUUAUAAUGGUACUAUUGAGAAGGAAAAGGCUACUACUCUAUGAAUUGGCCAGGAAGUCCUUCUCGUUCAUUCGGUAAAUACUCAUUGGAUACACUGCUAGAUGCCUCUCAGAGGGUGUCAUGCUCUGAUUGGGUCAUGAAGGACCAAUAGGAGUACACCAAGAGAACGGUCCCAUCUGAGAAGGAGUAUAUAUAGAGGCACAAGGACACGAUGUUUUUGGGAGAUCUACAGGUUGUUUAGGGUGACGGGUAGUGUAGGGCACAAGGGUAGAAGUAACGGGCAGUGAAGCUAGGCUCCAGAAACCAGCUUGACUGGAGUGCUCAUGUCUCUCUUCCAAGGUUCCUGUUAUUCGGACAGUGUUAGAUAAAAUGAUCGUAUUUCCUCUUGUGUGGGCUUCAUGGAGCUAACCACCUUCUGUUCACAAGUUCUUCACAUGAGUUCCAUUAGCUGGACUGUGGUUCAGCCCUCGUCAGUAUCCUAGUCCUUUCGAAUGUGGUGAUGACAGACUUUAUCACUGCAGGGGAUGGUGUUUCCUGUGUAUGUGAUGGGUUGGCAGGUGUCAACAGAUUCUUCUACCCCCCUCAGACGGAGUCUUACUCUGCCACCCAGGCUGGAGUGCAGUGGCACAAUCUUGGCUCACUGCAAUCUCUGCCUCCUGGGUUCAAACAAUUCUCUUGCCUCAGCCUCCUGAGUAGCUGGGAUUACAGGCACCUGCUACCACAGCCAGCUAAUUUGUUUGUAUUUUUAGUAGAGAUGGGGUUUCACCAUGUUGGCCAGGCUGGUCUCGAACUCCUGACCUCAUGAUCCAUCCGCCUUGGCCUCCCAAAGUGGUGGAAUUACAGGUGUGAGCCACCGCGCCUGGACAACGGAUUCUUUUAUUAAUGUUUAUUAAGGACUCAGGUGAAAUAUAAUGAAGUUAAAGACUAUUAAAAAAUAGUUGACAUCUCUAGCGUUCCCUGUUUUCAUUCAGAUUUGAUUACAAUCUGGAGUAGCCUGAUACAGUAUCUAUGAGCAUGUUCAUUGUUGGCAAUAUGGUACCUGUAGCAUUCUGGAACCUGAGGGGGUUUAGGGAUGAAUUAACCAAUAUCCUGUAAUACAGCCUUUACAUGGGUUGAGUCAGCUUAGUGUAGAUUAAUCAGGGAGCUACUUAGAGGGUUUUGUAAUGCUUCCUGGACCAGCUUCAUAUUUCACGUGUUGUCUGGAAGGUGGACCCACAUAAAUUGGAUUCAUUUUUCAAAGCAAGAAAGAAAUAGUUUAACCUUGAUGUUUUCCUUAAAAACAUGAUUGGCUAUAGUGUGAAAAGAAUGUAUAACUCUAUUUAUUAGGCAGUACAAUAUUAACAUCCCUCUGAACUUAUCUAGUUGGGUCUUACUAAAUGUAGUUCUGAGUUACAUUACUCAUUAGCAGUGUUCUAAAAUUGAAACAUUGAAGAAUCACUAAUUUUAGCUGUUUAUCUUAUUACUAACAAGUAGUUUAUUUUUUAGUUUUGUUUUUAAUAUUGCAGGAUCACAGUAGUAGAAGGGCAUUCACACAUCAUCUUGUCUAAUUAUUGCCUGUGUCACCUGAACAGCAGUGCCAUCUUUUGUGCCUCACUCAGUGGUUUUCAGUUGGGUGCCAUACUAGAAUAUCUGGGGAGGAACUUUUGAAACAAUUCAGGGCCUGGGCUCUCCCCUAGAUCAACUACAUCAGAAUCUUAGAGUGGGGCCUGGUUAUUGAUGUUUUUUAAAAAAAAAUUUACAGAUGAUUCUUAUAUGCAUCCAUAAUUGAGAGUGACUGAUUUAGAGUCUAGAUGCUCAACUAGUGUUUCUCAAACUUCAGUAUGCAACAUAACCACCUGGACUGCUAGUGAAAACACCUGGAAGGGCUACGUUGCUGGGCCCCAACCCCAGAAUGCCUGAUUGAGUAGGCCUGGGUGGGCCCCAGCAUUUUCAUUUCUAACAACUGCCCAGGGGAUGCUGAUGCUCCUAGUCCGGGAACACACUUUGAGAAUCAGUGAUCUAGAUCAGCGCUGUCCAGGGGAAAUAGAAUGUGAACCACGUAUGUGAUUUAAAAUUUUUCUAGUAACUACAUUAAAAAGAAACAGGUGAAACUAAUUUUAGUAUAUUUUAUUUAAGCUAUUGUAUCUAAAAUACUAUUUUGACAUACAAUUCAAUAUAAAAAUUAUUGAUCUCUCAUAUUUUCUUUUUCUUUUUCUUUUUUUUUUUUUUUUGGAGACAUUAGAGUUUGUUGUUGUUGCCCAGGCUGGAGUGCAAUGGCACGAUCUUGGCUCACUGGAACCUCUGCCUCCCAGGUUCAAGCGAUUCUCCUGCCUCGGCCUCCUGUGUAGCUGGGAUUACAGGCAUGCGCCACCAUACCUGGCUAAUUUUGUAUUUUUAGUAGAGACGGGGUAUCUCCGUGUUGGUCAGGCUGGUUUCAAACUGCUGACCUCAGGUGAUCCGCCUGCCUUGGCUUCCCAAAGUGCUGGGAUUACAGGCAUGAGCCACCGCACCCGGCUGAUGAUCUCUCAUAUUUUCUUAUAUGACCGCUUCAGAAUCUAGUAUUUUACACUGAUAGCACACCUCACUGUGGAUUAGCCACAUCAGAUGCUCAGUAGUCACAUGCGGUUAGCAACCACUAUUAAACAACACACAUCUAGACAAUUGCUGUGAAUUGCUAGUUAUAGAAAUUGGCAGAAUCCUGAGUCUAUAUAGUCUACCUCCGUAGAGCUAAGGUGAAAUUACCUUUUAUUUGCCAAAAUCUAUGUCUCUGUGGCUUCCAGGUUUUCGUUUUAUUAUACAGGUAUAAUUUUAAUUUCACAUGACAGUUGGAGGUAUUGAUCACGUCCCCCUGAGCCUUCUUUAGGCCAAACAUCACUAGUAGUUCUUCAUAUUGUAUUAAAGCCACAUCAUUUAUCUGAAUACGUCUCUCUUAAAAUACAGUAACUAGAAUGGUACCCAGUACCCUAUCUGGUCUGACCCCAAAUAAUAAAACCUUUUCCUUUUUCUGCACAUUUACUAUUAUUACUGCAGUCUAGAGAGCACGUUAGGUUUUUUGGUGCGUGUGUUGCAAUAUUGUCUAAUAGUAAAUUAUUGCGCACUCAAAACAUUUGCGUGCUCUUUAUGUAAUUGGUUGUUUUUGUGAACUCAAAUGCGAGACCUGCCAUAUAUCCCUAUAACACAGUGGUUCUCAAGCAGGGAUGAUUUUGCCCUCCAGGGGACAUUUGGCAAUGUCUAGAGACAUCUUUGGUUGUCACAACUGAUGGGGAGGGAGGUAGUGAUGUGCUACUGACAGCUAAUGGCAGAGGCCAAGUAUUCUCCUAAACUUCCUACAGUGCACAGGACAGCCUCCCACAACAAAAAAAUGAUCCUGGAAUGUCAAUAAUGUGGAGAUUGAGAAGCCCUGCUAUAGGUAAUGGUGAGAGUGUGAACUCAGGAAGUGGCCCAGAUCUCCUAGAGGCCCUUUGGGCAGCGGUGCUUUGUUCUCAUGAGUUUCUUGAGUGCUCUUAUUGGGCUCACCUAAGGAAACCCAGGUCACUGGAGUGUUUGUUCAUUACCUUGUAAUCCUGUCAGAAAAGGAAGUGAUUUGUCUAUUUUGGCUUGUUUUGGGUGAGCUCAAAGAAAGUUUGGUAAGUAAUGAAAAGCAUAUUAAAAAAUGUAACAAUUAAAACUCUUAAAUAUUAUUUUUAAUUCUGCUGCCUAGGGGUAACUAUGGCUAUCAUUUUGGUGUUGACAUUCGAGCGAGAGCCACGUUAUUUGGACUUGGAUCCUGGGCCUACCACUUACUAGUUUUGUGACCUUGGGCAGGUUUCCCCUGAGGGAUGGUAAUAGGACCUAUCUCAGAGUUGUGAGACACAACAUGUUUAAUACAUAUAAAGUGUUUAGGACAGUCCCUGGCACAUUGUAAGAACUAUUUAAGUGGUUGUUUCUGUGUGUUUUCUUGGCAUACGUUUGUGUGUGUUUCUGUGUCUGUGUAUGUGUAUAGUGUACAGAUGAACUUGGUUGAGUUCAUGUGGCAUAUACAGUUCUACACCUACUUUUUUGGAGAACAUUUGCUCAUGUUAUUAAAAGUUCCUAGCAAACAUGUAACUGUAGAAUACCAUGAAUUUUGGUACAUUAAAUGUAAAAUAACUACAUAAAUUUGUGAUAAAUCACAUCUCUUAAACUAAAUUCAAGAAUAGGCUAGUGGUGGCAGAUGCUGAUUAAGAAAAGUUUGAGGGAAAAGCUUGACAUUUAAAUUGUUUUAUCGAUUAACUUACUUUUCUCCAUGGUUGAAAAAAGACUGCCAUUGUCAGAUUUUAGCAAGACACCUCAGUCUAGCCUACAGAACUCUAUAUUCCACUCCUUCUAGAAUCUUGUCUUAGAUUGUUGGAAAGCUUCUUGGUUUUUAAUUUAUAGAAGCUGUCUUAAUUCUCCCCUCCCCUGCAAAAAAAAAAAAAGUAUAUAUUCUUAUACAUUAGAAGAGAUUCCAGCCUUUCUAUAGCUUUCUGUUGAAAAUUCACUUUUCUGAGUUGAAAAACAAAACCCCCUUUUUUCCUACACAUUUAGACAUGAAAUCUUUCUGAAAGUGAUGAGUUUAUACUUUGGAAUUACAGUAUCAUAGUUUUUCAUUUGGAAGAGUAAACAGUUGGGUGUAAAACUGGACAACUGUUUGGCUUCAGAAUUGUUUAUUUCUGUAGUUUUAAGGAUACCAGAUUGUGUUUGUCUUGUUUGAGUCUCUGUGUAUCUAAGCCUCUGUGUUUGUGAUAGUUCGGAAUUUAGAAGCCUUUGAGGGGUUUGAAAGUAAAGAUAACUCUUACAGUUUAUUACCAGUAUUUUAAUUUUAGAGAAACAAAAUGUGGUGUUUAAAGUUUUCAUUUGGCAGGAAUAACAAUGGCAUUGUUGCUCCCUGGGUGCUAAGUGAGGAGGCAAGGAGGAAGUGUCUUUCCAUAGUACAACUGUUUGUUGUCCAAGUGCUUUCCUUCUCAUGACUUUCUCCACUAUGUUCUUAGGACUCAAACAGAGUAUUGUUCAGUUGUUAGUAUUGGCAGCUUGACAAAUUGCUAUUUUUUGGGUACUAUUUGUUAAAUGAAUGAUUACUUAGCUGGGUAGCUGUAGUGGAACUUGUUUUAGAAAAGAGGCUGUAGAUAGGACAUGAUUUUGGAAGAGGAUCUGUAAAUCAUAGCCCUUAGGCAUGGAAUGGCCUAUAAGGUCUGGACCUUGUAGUAAGGUGGUUAGUGUAUCACCGGCUCCACUUGUUGAAGCAGCUGAGGCCCAGGGAAGUUUGAUGACUCUCCUGAGUCAGCCAGCUGGUACAUGGGGAAUAGAAUCCUUGUUUGCUGCCUCUCAAGAAGCAAUUGCUUGUUCAGAGCUCUUGGUGAUCAAUUGGAGGGACACUCACGAAAUCAUCUCAAGCACAGACAGGAGACAGUGGACUACAUGAUAAAGCAGCGGGAAGAUUUUGAACCCUUUGUAGAAGAUGACAUUCCUUUUGAGAAGCAUGUGGCCAGUUUGGCAAAGCCUGGUACUUUUGCUGGCAAUGAUGCAAUUGUAGCCUUUGCAAGAAAUCAUCAGUUGAAUGUAGUGAUUCAUCAACUUAAUGCCCCUUUGUGGCAGAUUCGUGGUACAGAGAAAAGCAGCGUGAGGGAGUUACACAUCGCAUAUCGGUAUGGAGAGCACUACGACAGUGUUCGGAGGAUCAAUGACAACUCAGAGGCACCUGCACAUCUCCAGACGGAUUUUCAGAUGCUUCAUCAAGAUGAAUCAAAUAAAAGAGAAAAGAUCAAGACAAAGGGAAUGGACUCUGAAGACGACCUGAGAGAUGAAGUAGAGGAUGCUGUCCAGAAAGUUUGUAAUGCAACUGGAUGUUCAGAUUUUAAUUUAAUAGUCCAGAACCUGGAAGCUGAAAAUUAUAAUAUUGAAUCUGCAAUAAUUGCCGUGCUUCGGAUGAACCAAGGGAAGAGAAAUAAUGCAGAAGAGAAUCUUGAGCCCAGUGGUCGAGUGCUGAAGCAGUGUGGCCCUUUGUGGGAGGAGGGUGGCAGUGGUGCCAGAAUCUUUGGAAAUCAGGGCUUAAAUGAAGGCAGGACCGAAAACAAUAAGGCACAGGCCAGCCCUAGUGAAGAAAACAAAGCAAAUAAAAACCAGCUCGCAAAGGUCACAAACAAACAGAGGCGAGAACAGCAGUGGAUGGAGAAGAAGAAGCGGCAGGAGGAGAGGCACCGCCACAAAGCCCUGGAGAGCAGAGGUAGCCACAGGGACAAUAACAGAAGCGAAGCAGAGGCGAACACGCAGGUCACCUUGGUGAAGACCUUCGCCGCUCUCAACAUCUGACUCUUUGGCCUCUUGGGAGUUGUAAGAAGCGGCUGGAAAAGGAUUGCUGUGUGCUAGACUUUCCAGUGAGGCCGUCCUUUUAUAAAACGCAACACAACCAACGAAGCCCACACAUGAGCUCACACACUGAGUUAGUUUCGUUCAAGCUGCCUCUUUUUUUGUUCGAAGUUUUAUUAGUGAUAUGUUGGUGUUUUAUGAAAAUGCAGUGAGGCCAUUCAUAUUCUGUAAUACAAAAUUAAAAUACUGAGUUUUAGGGGCAGAUAGUUAGGUCAGGAAAAACCUUUUAAGUGGUGGCUUUAUUUGCCCUGAAAAUCAGACUUCAGUGACCCUAGGAUCUUUCCUUAACAUUUGGGGUGAGUUUUGCUGUAAUUGUUCAUGAGUAGUUUAGAAUAAUUGUUAGAAAUUCAGAAUGACAAGUUUCCUUAGUUUCUCUUUCAUUCUCAAACAGAUAUAUAGGGUAGCUUAUAAAUGAUCUCCAACUCAGGAAUAUGCUUUGAUUUACUUCUAAUCCAAGUUACUCAGAAAAUAAUUCAGGAAUUGUUUUCCCAAAGUUACGUGAGGGUUGUGGCCUGCAGUCAGGAUGGAAAUUAACCGCAUUUCUCUCCUUCCUGAUUCUGAUGUUAUUUCAGAUGGGAUGCAGGUGCUGUUAGUUCAUUUGCACUCAAGCCAUAUGAUAAAUGCAGCUGACUGUUAAUUAGGCCUGGCCUUGUUGGGAAGUUGAUAGUGGUGUUGGGUUUUUGGUAUUUGUUUCCUGACAGUGGGGAGAUGGCAUGUUACUGCUUGUGAUACAGUUCUGGAAUUCUGAUAGUGUGUAGAGCAGGGUCUAUAGUUGUAACAGGAGACGAACUCCUGGGGUUUUGCCUAAGAGGAGUCUAAAGAAUUAUGUUUUUAUAGGAGAAGCCUGGAAGAAUAAGGUUUUUCAUGUUCGCAUUUUAAAUAACGAUUUUCUUCCCUUCUGUUGUAGACUUAGAUGCCUUCAGAGAGAUACGUGGUAACUUGACCUUAUAGGUCGCUAAACUUAGUAUUGUGGAAAUUAAAUCUUAUAAAAUGCUACAUUUAUUUCUUUUUAUUUAAGCCCUGUUUGGCAUUUCAAAGUUGGGAAAACUCCAGCAUCUGCUGGAAGUUGUUGGACCAGCAGGGUUGGUUGACUUAGGUUGGACCAGCAGAGAAGAGAACAUACUUUGGUUGAGGCCUUCGAAUCACUCUUCAGUUCUGAAAUAGACAGACUUGAGCAGUGGAGAGACGUCUUUCCUAAAACUGAGUUAGGUGGAUGUGAACUUAAGAACUAUAACGUAUGAGGCAGCCCAUCUUGGAUCAUCUUUGUCUUUUGGGACCUAAUACUUGGGCAAAUAAUUGAUGCUGAGUUGAAAGGUAAAUUAUUAGUUAUCUUCCCCACCCCUCGCAUUUCAGAAUUAUAAAAAUUCGGAGGCAAAUUGAAAACUAAAAUGUUUGGUAGGCCCUGGAGUCGCCAGAUUGUCUUUAUCACCAGGCCUUUGGCUUUCUUCAGUUUCACUGGUAUCUUUUGGUUUUGUUUUUGACUUUGGUGGCUUUUUGUAGUUGGAGCAUCAGUAGUCUCUUGGAAUUGCUCCUAGGACAUUGUGGUUUAGGUUUCUUCCUGGGUACAGUACAUUGUAAAAUUUAGCAGAUUAAAAAAAGUACACAGCAUUUUUUUUCUGUGCACGUCGCAGAGUCCUGAGCUUGAGGCUGUGUUACUCUACUCAUUCCAAACGAAUGAAAGAUCUCUGUUGCCUUACUCUAAGGAAGUGGGAUCGAGUGCGUUAGGAUCUAUGGUUGUCUUGGUUUUCAACUCUGGGCAGAUUCCUGACUGGCUGAGUGUUUCUGAAUGAAGAUGUUUUCCUGUCUGUUUUGUACUGCUUGAGUGCAGAGGCCAGAUCCUCUCAGAAAGAUAAGAUUGUAUGCCAGAAAUUCAGAUUAGCAGUCAGCUUAAGAGAGACUUAUUGUCAGAAGUAGUAGAAUUGCUUUAUUUACUUGGUUAAUGAAGGUGGCCUUGGGCCCUAUUGGGUUUUAGAAGUUUUAGAAGCUGCUAAAAAGUUAUUAAAGAAUAUUGGGAACAUUUAUUUUUUAAAUUACCUAAUUCUGGUAAUAGGCUUCAGCAUUUCUGGAGUAUAAUAAUGGUGGUUUAAAAAACUAAUCAAACGGCUUUAGUAAUUUUACUACUGGUUUCACAGCUUUUCAGUUACAGUUGGUCUGUUUAGUGUGUUAAUUAUUAGGAAUCGGGUACAUGCAUCCAACUUCAGUGAUACCUUCUAGCUAAUGGUUUCAAUUUAGACUUCACUGCCUCAGUCUCACUGGGUACAUGAGAAGGUUGGAAUCAACAUGCUUAGUUGCCUCAGUGGGCACUUGAAAAUUCCUUCACUGGCAGCCCGAGUGGAGGCCCAGUAUGUCUAGUCCUGGGAUGACUGUUGUCAGCAGCUGUUACUCUAGUACAGGUGCUCCUGUGAACUCUUUAUUAGGAACUGAAUGUGUCUUAACCUCUGUGUUACAUCUUGGCUGGCAGAGAUUUAUGUUACAUGAGAUUGUCUUGGUAGCUUGUAGUGUGGUCAGGAGAAAGGGGAUGGAGCAGUGGUGCAUAGCUGCUUACUGCUCUUAUAAACGGUAUAUAAAGGUUUUACGGAUUUUGAAAAUAUUUUUUUUUAGAGGUCAAAAUAAAUACCAUUUUAGUGGCAACAGCUUUGAACUAGAGAGGUAGAUGUAUUAAAGCAGCAUAGAACCAUAACUUCUAGAUAAUGUAGUUGCCACUAGGAGAUAUUAGAAAGUUAGAAUGUAUGUGUGUAUUUAGUUUUUCAAUAAUAAUGAACAUACACUUUCAGGAGCAAAGUAUGGUUGAGAAAUUGUGGCAGAAAGAAUUUUAAAUGUUAGUCGAAGUUGUCUGUAGUUUCUUUAUUAAGCUCUGAAAACACUUCCAAUGCCAGUUUGAUUCUGAGGGCUUGGGAAGUGGGAUCUCCCUUGUGGAGCAGCUGGAGCUGGCUGGGAGGGAGCCUCUCCAUGGGUAAUUUAUUAUGCCUGCCCUGCUUCCCCCAGGGAGCUGCUUCAGUGUGAAAUGAUGUGAUUGUCGGGGGUGGGGUGGGAGGAGGGCCACCUUCAGUCGGGGAGUUGCUCACAUAUUACACAGGUAGCAUCAGGUGGACUUCAGCGCUGAACUGUACUAGUAGUGAGUCCCUGUAGUCAAUGUGCAAUUUCUCUAAUUCUGAGAAACUCUGUAGACUCUGCCUGGGUUUUACUGGGUCAGCAUAGAAUGCUAUCAGUUUACCUCUGUGAAAUAUUCAGUCAGUUGAAGGAAACUUGGAUUCCUAGUCAGAGGUGACUAAAAGUUACCCUGACCAAAAGGAUCUCUGCGGGGGGAAGAGAAUGGAGCUUCCUGAUUUUAAUGUGUUGCGUCAGUGGCCCUCUUCGACUCCCGUUUUGGGUAGAUGCGUAGCUCUUCACUUUCUUACCUCAAGGCUCUGUCUAGCCAUGUUAAAUCUUUAGACUCAGUCUGAUGCCGUUUUUCUGUUUUGCCAUUCUCAUUAUUCACAGCUUUCAGAACAAGUGUUGCUAAAACUCCGGGGCCUUUGACAGUUGUUCUGAGGUGAUUUAAUAAUGGACUUUUUAUAAGUUAUGUUUUCCUGGCUCUAAAGUAAAUUUUUUUUUUUUUUUUUUUGAGACAGAGUCUUGCUUUGUUGCCCAGGCUGGAGUGUGGUGGGGCAAUCUCGGCUCACUGCAACCUCCACCUCCCGGGUUCAAGCGAUUCUCCUGCCUCAGCCUCCUGAGUAGCUGGGAUUACAGGUGUGUGCCACCAUGCUUGGCUAAUUUUUGUAUUUUUAGUAGAGACGGGGUUUCACCAUGUUAGCCAGGCUGGUCUCAAACUCCUGACCUUGUGAUCUGCCCGCCUCAGCCUCCCAAAGUGCUAGGAUUACGGGUGUGAGCAACCCUGCCCGGCCAGUAAAUUGUAUUUUUUUAAUGACAUCAUUGAUUUGAAGAUCUAGAUGGCAUAAAUUACGACGUCUGCCAUCGCAUAUUAGAAAGGGGACAGUCAUAUUUGUAACGUGGAGAGAACACGGAGCACCAGUCACCACGUGCACUUAGGAUGCAGAGCUUACCGCACACCGCUGAUGGGGACCUCCGGAAAGAGCGGUGCCUUGUGGUUGGCCUGGAAGUUCUCUCCCAAGGUGAAAUUCCUUUAAAACCUCAGGCUCUGACCUAUGUCUUUGAAGCAGCUGCUUUGUAGAGUCCCUCUCUUUACUGUCCUCGUUAGGACUGUUUUGUGGUUCCAUGAAAAUGUUUAGCAUCCUUGCAGAAUUACUUGAGAAGGGGCUGGUACCAGUGUAAAGAAUCUAUUUCUGUAAAACUACGAACUUUUGCAUAGGGAAUUUAUUCUAAGCAGGUCAUAGCCGUGAUCCAGAGCUGCUGCUGCUCACUGCCAGUCCUUGCGGCUGGCGGCGAUUGCCGGACAGACUCUCUGUGGCCUGGCUCUCAUCCUUGGCGUGUCAGCCUGCGGCAGGCUGCCAGCCAUCCAUGACAAUCAUGUGAGCUCAGCCACAGACCUCAGCUGGCGGUUUGAUCCCUGGCAGGUCCCUCGAGCAGUACUGGUAAGAGGCUUCACACAUUUUCCCACUCUUACAGUUCAUUUUUCAUAGUAGGAAGGGCCCUUGGCCUCCCCAGUGCCUCUUCCAGAGCCUCCACCAGCACUAAGCUCAGAGGAAAGAAGAAAAGGGCCAGGAGUCAGACGUCACACCCGGGGGCUCCCCUUUCCCAUGUAGAAGUGUUGGCAUGCGUCAGUCUCCUUUACAGAGGGGUGGAUGUAUCCGUGGAGGAGGGGCCUUCUCUCUUUCUAAUUGCACUAUACUUGUUCUAGCUUCAGUCUGGAGAUACUUAAGACCUCCAUGGGGUCGUGAUCCAUAGACUUAGCAAGUCUUGCCUUAUCUAUGGAGCUCGAUGGUGAGAAUUGUGACCAUUGUCUGAUGUCCAUAGUUCCUUCCCCCUAGAUUGUUUCUUUCCACGGAUUGUGUUCAUCUGAACCAUUUUAUUUUUUAUUUACCAAAGUACUGUACUUGGCUAUUUGCAGUGUUUUCAAAACCAAAUGUUUCUUUUUUUGUGUUUUUAAUCUUCGAUACUUGGUGCAAUAGAAGCUGCAAAGAUGUGCCACUUUAUCUAUGAAAUGGAGUUUUGUAUACCAAUAAAUUCUAGUUUAAAAACAAA